AUGAAGGCCGAGAACCGCUGCCGCCGCCGACCCCCGCCGGCCCUGAACGCCAUGAGCCUGGGUCCCCGCCGCGCCCGCUCCGCUCCGACUGCCGUCGCCGCCGAGGCCCCCGUUGAUGCCGCUGAGCUCCCCCAACGCCGCCGCCACCGCCUCCGACAUGGACAAGAACAGCGGCUCCAACAGCUCCUCCGCCUCUUCGGGCAGCAGCAAAGGGCAACAGCCGCCCCGCUCCGCCUCGGCGGGGCCAGCCGGCGAGUCUAA